GUGCGUCUCGCGCCGCCGCCGCCCGCCGCGUGAGAGGACGGGCUCCGCGCGCUCCGGCAGCGCAUUCGGGUCCCCUCCCCCCGGGAGGCUUGCGAAGGAGAAGCCGCCGCAGAGGAAAAGCAGGUGCCGGUGCCUGUCCCCGGGGGCGCCAUGGCGACCGGAGCGAACGCCACGCCGUUGGGUAAGCUGGGCCCCCCCGGGCUGCCCCCGCUCCCCGGGCCCAAAGGAGGCUUCGAGCCGGGCCCUCCGCCUGCACCCGGGCCUGGGGCGGGGCUGCUGGCUCCCGGGCCGCCGCCGCCCCCGCCCGUGGGCUCGAUGGGGGCCCUGACCGCGGCCUUCCCCUUCGCGGCGCUGCCUCCGCCGCCUCCGCCGCCGCCCCCUCCGCCUCCCCAGCAGCCGCCGCCGCCUCCACCGCCACCGUCCCCCGGCGCCUCGUACCCGCCGCCGCAGCCGCCCCCUCCGCCGCCGCUCUACCAGCGCGUGUCGCCGCCGCAGCCGCCGCCACCCCAGCCGCCGCGUAAGGACCAGCAGCCGGGCCCGGCCGGCGGCGGAGGAGACUUCCCAAGUAAGAAGCGGAAGAGGAGCCGCUGGAACCAAGACACAAUGGAACAGAAGACAGUGAUUCCAGGAAUGCCUACAGUUAUUCCCCCUGGACUUACUCGAGAACAAGAAAGAGCUUAUAUAGUGCAACUGCAGAUAGAAGACCUGACUCGUAAACUGCGCACAGGAGACCUGGGCAUCCCCCCUAACCCUGAGGACAGGUCCCCUUCCCCUGAGCCCAUCUACAAUAGCGAGGGGAAGCGGCUUAACACCCGAGAGUUCCGCACCCGCAAAAAGCUGGAAGAGGAGCGGCACAACCUCAUCACAGAGAUGGUUGCACUCAAUCCGGAUUUCAAGCCACCUGCAGAUUACAAACCUCCAGCAACACGUGUGAGUGAUAAAGUCAUGAUUCCACAAGAUGAGUACCCAGAAAUCAACUUUGUGGGGCUGCUCAUCGGGCCCAGAGGGAACACCCUGAAGAACAUAGAGAAGGAGUGCAAUGCCAAGAUUAUGAUCCGGGGGAAAGGGUCUGUGAAAGAAGGGAAGGUUGGGCGCAAAGAUGGCCAGAUGUUGCCAGGAGAAGAUGAGCCACUUCAUGCCCUGGUUACUGCCAAUACAAUGGAGAACGUCAAAAAGGCAGUGGAACAGAUAAGAAACAUCCUGAAGCAGGGUAUCGAGACUCCAGAGGACCAGAAUGAUCUACGGAAGAUGCAGCUUCGGGAGUUGGCUCGCUUAAAUGGGACCCUUCGGGAAGACGAUAACAGGAUCUUAAGACCCUGGCAGAGCUCAGAGACCCGCAGCAUUACCAACACCACAGUGUGUACCAAGUGUGGAGGGGCUGGCCACAUUGCUUCAGACUGUAAAUUCCAAAGGCCUGGUGAUCCUCAGUCAGCUCAGGAUAAAGCACGGAUGGAUAAAGAAUAUUUGUCCCUCAUGGCUGAACUGGGUGAAGCACCUGUCCCAGCAUCUGUGGGCUCCACCUCUGGGCCUGCCACCACACCCCUGGCCAGCGCACCUCGUCCUGCUGCUCCCGCCAACAACCCACCUCCACCGUCUCUCAUGUCUACCACCCAGAGCCGCCCACCCUGGAUGAAUUCUGGCCCUUCAGAGAGUCGGCCCUACCACGGCAUGCAUGGAGGUGGUCCUGGUGGGCCCGGAGGUGGCCCCCACAGCUUCCCACACCCAUUACCCAGCCUGACAGGUGGGCAUGGUGGACAUCCCAUGCAGCACAACCCCAAUGGACCCCCACCCCCUUGGAUGCAGCCACCACCACCACCGAUGAACCAGGGCCCCCACCCUCCUGGGCACCAUGGCCCUCCUCCAAUGGAUCAGUACCUGGGAAGUACGCCUGUGGGCUCUGGGGUCUAUCGCCUGCAUCAAGGAAAAGGUAUGAUGCCGCCACCACCUAUGGGCAUGAUGCCGCCGCCGCCGCCGCCUCCCAGUGGGCAGCCCCCACCCCCUCCCUCUGGUCCUCUUCCCCCAUGGCAACAACAGCAGCAGCAGCCUCCGCCACCCCCUCCGCCCAGCAGCAGUAUGGCUUCCAGUACCCCCUUGCCAUGGCAGCAAAAUACGACGACUACCACCACGAGCGCUGGCACAGGGUCCAUCCCGCCAUGGCAACAGCAGCAGGCGGCUGCCGCAGCUUCUCCAGGAGCCCCUCAGAUGCAAGGCAACCCCACUAUGGUGCCCCUGCCCCCCGGGGUCCAGCCGCCUCUGCCGCCUGGGGCCCCUCCCCCUCCGCCGCCUCCACCGCCUGGUUCCGCCGGCAUGAUGUAUGCCCCGCCCCCUCCUCCUCCGCCUCCCAUGGACCCUUCUAACUUUGUCACCAUGAUGGGCAUGGGGGUGGCGGGCAUGCCGCCCUUCGGGAUGCCUCCAGCUCCCCCACCGCCUCCACCACAGAACUAGACUUGUUUUUUAAGAAAAUAUAUAUUAUAUAUAGAGAGAAUUGGUCUCGUUUAAACACGCCGAACCUCACCAUAUGGAGCCAGACAUUGGGACGCACGCAUGUGAUUGUGUGUGCACGCAUGUGUGUGUGUGCACGCACUGGGCUGGGCCAAGCGACUGAGGAUUCGCUUGGGAACGGGCAGGUGGUAGUAGGGGCGCCAGCUUGGGCUCUCCUGGCGCCCCGUAGCAUCGAGUGUCUUCUUUGUCUUCUUUCUCUCCUCACCCAACUCCCUUUGCCUCUCCCCAAACCGGGCCGCCAGGAUCCCUCCCCGCGGCGGCGAUGGCCCGAGCCAUGAGAGUGAGGACUUUCCGCGCCCAUUGGUGACCCUUCCAGGCAGACAGCCUCAGCAACGCCCCUGGUGGACAGGAUGGUUCGGCAAAGCAGCCUGAGUUAUUUUUGUGGACGGAAUCGGAACACGCUGGCUCCAUAUCGUGAAAUUUUUAUUAAUUUUUUUCUUUUUCCUUUGUUACUUCUUUAUCUUUUCCUUUCUUCAGACUCCGUCCAAGGAGAUGCUCUCCCCGGUCUUCUGCUGCAAUUUAGAUUCCUUUCCCUUCUCUCCAGUUCUCCUUCCCUUACCAAGGAGAGGGGAGCAAAUGGUUUUGGGCAAGGGCUUUGGCCAUUCAUGUCAAGCUGGUUGUGGGUUUUUCAAGGUGCCAUAGCCACCCCCAAAGAUGUUUGUUUAAAGCGUGGGGUUUUUUAAUCUCUGCCACCCUUGUCAAGGGAGUCUUGUAAAGUUGCCGAGGGUAGGUUCAUCUCCAGGUUUCGGGAUUCCCAUCCGUCCUGGCGAUCCUGCCAGCAGUGGGUGGGCAGCCUGAGCUCCCUCGGGCUCGCCUGCCAGCCUGGAGUUCUUCCUGUGCUCCUUGAUCACCUGAGCUGCCUCAGAUUCCAUUUGGUCCUCUCCUUCCUGGAAGGCUUCCUUUUAUGUUUUGUUUUAAUCCCAAAUGUCUGAAUGUUUUGCAGUGUGUAGGGGUUUGAGCCCCUUGUUCAUUCUCCUUCCUUUUUCCUCCCGCUUCCCUCUCCAUGAAGUGAUUCUGUUGACAAUAAUGUAUACUGCGCGUUCUCUUCACUGGUUUAUCUGCAGAAAUUUCUCUGGGCUUUUUUCGGUGUUAGAUUCAACACUGCGCUAAAGCGGGGAUGUUCCAUUGAAUAAAAGAGCAGUGUGGUUUUCUGGG